AUUCCUCAGGACACAGAGCUUCCUCUCUCCCAGGAGCCAUGAAUAUCCUGAUGCUGACCUUCAUUAUCUGUGGGUUGCUAACUCGGGUGACCAAAGGUAGCUUUGAACCCCAAAAAUGUUGGAAGAAUAAUGUAGGACAUUGCAGAAGACGAUGUUUAGAUACUGAAAGGUACAUACUUCUUUGUAGGAACAAGCUAUCAUGCUGCAUUUCUAUAAUAUCACAUGAAUAUACUCGACGACCAGCAUUUCCUGUGAUUCACCUAGAGGAUAUAACAUUGGAUUAUAGUGAUGUGGACUCUUUUACUGGUUCCCCAGUAUCUAUGUUGAAUGAUCUGAUAACAUUUGACACAACUAAAUUUGGAGAAACCAUGACACCUGAGACCAAUACUCCUGAGACUACUAUGCCACCAUCUGAGGCCACUACUCCCGAGACUACUAUGCCACCAUCUGAGACUGCUACUUCCGAGACUAUGCCACCACCUUCUCAGACAGCUCUUACUCAUAAUUAAUUAACAUUUACUUCUGGUAUGGAACAACUAGAAAUACUGCUGGAAAUAAUAUCCAAAGAGCUGAUUCUACCAAUCCAAUUUCACCAGGAAAAUUCCAUCAGGGAUUGGAUGACCAUGGGGAUGGACAUAAUUGCUACUACCAACACAACAGCCAAGAGAGUUGCCUUACAAUUAGAAAUGUGUAGACAGAAAUGUAUAGAAGAUACAAGGAUUCUCUUAAUUGGACUUAAAUUCUUUAUCUGUCUUCCUCCGAUGUACUCAAAUAUAUGAGCUAAUUUUUGUCUUAAGUGAACAUUUGUAUAUCUAUGUAUUUUUCCAUGCCAAAAACAAAAACGAAGACCAUUGUUUGGAGCUGCCUCUUAUGACUAAGACAAGAAUUUUUACUUUAACAGUGCCUGGCCCACUACUAUCGUAUAUAGGAGAACAUAUAAAAGCAUAUAGAAAGUUCCAGAUGAAUGUUCCCUUCUCUACCCUCCACCUUUUAUUGUAAGUUCUGACCCUAAAUACUUUUCUGUGUCAUGACGUCAAAUUUUGUUUAAGGUUCUAGCUGGUAACUAACAGAGUCAGAAGCUAAUUCUUUCAUUCAACACAAGCACUGAUCUAACUGGAUAGAGAUAAAAGUGGGACUUGCCUUGAGAGUACAUCAUAUUAAAUUAAAAGCUGCAUCUCAAAUUCUA